AGGCUCCUGGAGUCGAAUCCAAAUCACUCAUUGUGAAAGCUGAGCUCACAGCCGAAUAAGCCACCAUGAGGCUGUCAGUGUGUCUCCUGAUGGUCUCGCUGGCCCUUUGCUGCUACCAGGCCCAUGCUCUUGUCUGCCCAGCUGUUGCUUCUGAGAUCACAGUCUUCUUAUUCUUAAGUGACGCUGCGGUAAACCUCCAAGUUGCCAAACUUAAUCCACCUCCAGAAGCUCUUGCAGCCAAGUUGGAAGUGAAGCACUGCACCGAUCAGAUAUCUUUUAAGAAACGACUCUCAUUGAAAAAGUCCUGGUGGAAAUAGUGAAAAAAUGUGGUGUGUGACAUGUAAAAAUGCUCAACCUGGUUUCCAAAGUCUUUCAACGACACCCUGAUCUUCACUAAAAAUUGUAAAGGUUUCAACACGUUGCUUUAAUAAAUCACUUGCCCUGCA